GGGGGCUCGAGGCGCCUCCGCGGCCGUGGACGAGCGUCCGUGCGGCCUGGUCCGGGCCAUGUCCGCGUGAGGACCCCGCCGCUGUCGCCGCUCCCGUUCCGGCCCUGGCCCCUCUGCCCGGCAGCGCCGCGCACCAUGGGCUCCAUUCUCAGCCGCCGCAUCGCGGGGGUGGAGGACAUCGACAUCCAGGCGAACUCGGCCUAUCGCUACCCUCCGAAGUCCGGAAACUACUUUGCUUCGCACUUUUUCAUGGGAGGAGAGAAAUUCGACACCCCCCACCCUGAAGGUUACCUCUUUGGAGAGAACAUGGAUCUGAACUUCCUGGGCAGCCGCCCGGUCCAGUUUCCCUACGUCACUCCUGCCCCCCACGAGCCCGUGAAGACGCUGCGGAGCCUGGUGAACAUCCGCAAAGACUCCCUGCGGCUGGUGAGGUACAAAGACGAUGCCGACAGCCCCACCGAGGACGGCGACAAGCCCCGGGUGCUCUACAGCCUGGAGUUCACCUUCGACGCCGAUGCCCGCGUGGCCAUCACCAUCUACUGCCAGGCAUCGGAGGAGUUCCUGAACGGCAGGGCAGUAUACAGCCCCAAGAGCCCCUCGCUACAGUCCGAGACCGUCCACUACAAGAGAGGGGUGAGCCAGCAGUUCUCCCUGCCCUCCUUCAAGAUUGACUUCUCGGAAUGGAAGGAUGACGAGCUGAACUUUGACCUGGACCGGGGCGUGUUUCCAGUAGUCAUCCAGGCUGUGGUGGACGAAGGAGAUGUGGUGGAAGUGACUGGCCACGCCCACGUGCUCUUGGCUGCCUUUGAAAAGCACAUGGACGGCAGCUUCUCUGUGAAGCCUUUAAAGCAGAAGCAAAUUGUGGACCGGGUCAGCUACCUCCUGCAGGAGAUCUAUGGCAUUGAGAACAAGAACAACCAGGAGACCAAGCCCUCGGACGACGAGAACAGCGACAACAGCAACGAGUGUGUGGUGUGCCUGUCCGACCUGCGGGACACGCUGAUCCUGCCCUGCCGCCACCUGUGCCUCUGUACCUCCUGCGCCGACACGCUGCGCUACCAGGCCAACAACUGCCCCAUCUGCCGGCUGCCUUUCCGGGCCCUCCUGCAGAUCCGGGCGGUGCGGAAGAAGCCAGGAGCCCUGUCCCCCGUGUCCUUCAGCCCCGUCCUGGCCCAGAGCCUGGAGCAUGAUGAGCACUCUUGUCCCUUUAAAAAAUCAAAGCCGCACCCCGCCUCCCUGGCCAGCAAGAAACCUAAAAGGGAAACAAACUCUGACAGCGUCCCACCUGGCUACGAGCCCAUCUCGCUGCUCGAGGCGCUCAACGGCCUCCGGGCUGUCUCCCCGGCCAUCCCCUCGGCCCCUCUUUAUGAAGAAAUCACCUAUUCAGGCAUCUCGGACGGCCUGUCCCAGGCCAGCUGUCCCCUCGCGGCUAUCGACCACAUCCUGGACAGCAGCCGCCAGAAGGGCAGGCCGCAGAGCAAGGCCCCCGACAGCACCCUACGGUCCCCGUCUUCCCCCAUCCACGAAGAGGAUGAGGAGAAGCUCUCCGAGGACGUGGACGCCCCUCCCCCACUGGGUGGCGCAGAGCUGGCCCUGCGGGAAAGCAGCUCCCCUGAGAGUUUCAUAACAGAAGAGGUUGAUGAGUCGUCGUCACCACAGCAAGGGACCCGAGCAGCUUCCAUUGAGAAUGUCCUGCAGGACAGCAGCCCCGAGCACUGUGGCCGAGGCCCACCUGCUGACAUCUACCUGCCAGCCCUGGGGCCCGACUCCUGCUCUGUUGGUAUAGACGAGUAAGCCGGUACGUGACCUCCCAGACGCGCUUCGGGGGCUCUGACGCGCGUCCUUGGAGAGAGGAGCCCUCCCCUGCUCUCUGGCGGGGGUUCCUUCUGGUUUUUGGGUCUUCGUCCGCAUCCGCAUCUUCCCAGGGGCCCUGGAUUCCGAAUCCAGAGCUCUCCAGUGGCUGCUGCACCUUCCCCCAGAAAGUGGCCUCCUGGGGGGUCCUGACUUUCGGGGCCAGAGGUCUCUCCAUCUGGACUAGGCGGCCGGUCAGGCUCUUCUUCCAGCCUUGAGGGGCCCUGGAACAGUCCCAGCCCAGGCAGGGAGACAGACACAGCCCAGGUGCGCCAGAGCCACUGUCCACUGCGGGAGGCAGGAGCUUGAGGGAUGAGGGCAGCACCGUGGAGGGAACCCCAGGGAGACAUGGGGUGAGCGUCCCAAGGGGAGAGGCCUGGGCCUGGCCUUGUUCCGGAUGGUCCCACCAUGAGUUCGCAUCGGUCCUGCAGCAGACACGUUAGGACGCUCAGCAGGUCCACUCCCGUGUUCCGGUCGUGGCUUUAACAAUUCAUGGGGAAAGAAUGCGCCCCGAUUGGGAGAGCCCCUGGAUCACGUCUUCCCAAGCUCAGUCCCUGUCUCUUGGAGGGAGUCCGUCCUCGAGGGGCCCUCUGGUGCCCAGGGGAGAGUAUCUUGCGUCCUGUCCUGAGGGCGUCCGCUCACACAGCCACCUGCUCCCCCGCUCCCUCCUUCCCUUGUCAGCAUGGCCACCGUGGGCCUGGCAUCACCAUGGGCCUGGCACACAGUCCCUCGUGGGCUGCCUUUGUGCCAUGAGCCCACUGCUGCCGACUCACCUGUCCCUCCCAGUACUGGAACCUUCUGGAACACCAGCACUAAAAGAUAGGAGGCCCUGUGAGGUUGGCAUCCCCCAUCCCCCCCAAGAGGCGCCCUCUACCAGGGUGGCCCAGGUGAGUGUUUUACAGAAGGCGGCUCUGUCCAGGCAGUGGUUCGCACCUAUAAGCCCGGUACUUUGGGAGACCGAGGGGAUAGAUCACUUGAGCCCAGGAAUUCAAGAUCAGUGUAGAAAACAUAGACCCCCUCUCUAUGAAAAAUAAAAAAUUGGCUUGGGCGUGGUAGCUUGUGCCUGUGGUCCCAGCUACUCAGGGGUGCUGAGGUGGGAGGAUUGCCGGAGCUGGGGAGGUCAAGGCCCACUCCAGCCUGAGACGCUGUCUCAAUAAAAAAAAAUACACACACACCCACCCACCCACUCCAGCCUGAGACCCUGUCUCAAGAAAAAAAAAAUACACACACACACACACACACACACACACACGGGGGAGAGAGAGAAGGCAGCUCCAGGAGUGCCACCAAAAUGUAGGCAGACGGAUUGGGGACCCUCUGCCUUCCCAGAGGGUCUUGGCACACAAGCUGCGUGCAGCUCUGGUCUGCCGAGGCCCAUGCAGCCUGCUGGGAGGUGCCUGGCCGGGGGUGCAGGCUCUAAGAGGCCCUUUCCCCUUGGGUGGACUUGAGCCGGGUCAGGGAGAACUUCGCUUCUUUUGACUGCGCUCUGCAUUCCCAUGAACCUCUGUCUUCUUGAGCCCAGCGAGUCCCUCUGUUGACCCCUGUCCUGAGCCAUUAUACCCCUAGAUUGAAACAGUCAGCACCUUUCAGACGGCCCCGGCCUGCGCAUCGGUGGAAGGUGCCGUGCGAAUGUCACGAUUCAGGUCAAGCUUCCGGAGCUGGGGAGUGCAGGUGUGAUCUAGAACAGGGCUCACAGCCUCGGAAACCUGCUCUCGCCGCGGCCCCCGAAGAAAAUAGACGCCCUUCACCGGAGAGUGGGGCCUGGGCCGUGUCUGCUGGGAGCCAUGUGUCAGGGCUGGUGGCUGGGUGUCAGGCAGCCCUGAGGCCAUGCUGGCCCCGUCCCAGGCUCUGCACCAGCACCAUUGCCCAAGCCCCAGGGACGCCAGACCCAUCUGGGGACAGCGCCCGGCGGCGUCGUGCAGGCCACAGUCUGGGCAUUGGGGCUCUGUGGGAGGCUCCUCUCUUUGCCUUGCAGUAGCCAUCCGGGGGCUACUCUGAGCACGGGCUUGUUCUCACCCAGGGCCGCUCCCCACCCCUGCACCCUGGGUUGACCGAGUUCCACCCUAACCCAGCCGUAAGAACCUUGGCAGGACAGUGGCUGGCCACAUCCCAGGAAACCGGAACCAGGGCAAGGGCAGGAGGCCCAGAGGGCAUCCACCGCGGUGCCGUGUCGCGCUCUGACUCGGGGCUGCAGAUCUGCUGUGGGUGUCCGGGGAUCUGGGAUCGUCUGUCCCAAGAGGGACACAGCGUAUUUGGCACAGUUAGGGAGUCCCCGGGCCCUUGGUGUGCUCACAUCUGAGUGAAUGCUGUUGUGGCCACAGGCGGCGGGAGUGGGGGUGCUGGAUGGCCCAGCCCCUCUGGGGCUCCAGAUCGGUAGGAGCGGGUGGCGUGGCACCAGGCAUCCGAGUGUGACCCUCCUCCCUCUGCUCCCACCUGCAGGACGGCCCACCUCCAUGGAGACGGCCCACGGCCUCGCCACCACCAGCCCCACCUGGCCUCCACUUGGUGGCCCCAGCCCCGAUCCCAGCGCCGCCGAGCUGACCCCACUCUGAGAGCCUGGCCGAGCUGGCAGCAUGGAGCCCUCGGCUCCCCAGACUUUGCCGAGGGGCUGCUCCGGACCCCGUUGUGAGCCGGCCUCCUGUCUGCAUGCCCCCUGUGGCCACCAGGCUCCGAGGGGCCGUGGUGACUCUUGAUCAAAGAGCACAGUGAACUGUCCCUUCUGAGUCUCCCUUUUCUACAGUUGAUAUAUUUGUAACUGGUACAAGAUGAAGGACAGCAGCUUUCCAUCCCUAGUUCAGAGCCCCCGUUCCCCAGGGUCCUGUGGGCUGAGCGGCUGGGGCUGGGGCUGCCCACGUGUGGCCUCCGCUGGCUCUGCCUGCUCCUGCAACAGUGCGGUCCCUGCCCGGAGAACUCAGGAGGCCUGCAGAAGAGAACUGAUUGGUGGUCGAAGCACCAUCUUCACAGAUGUUCAGGGGCAGUGGGGGGCUCCAGGCACGGUCAAUGAAGGAAACAGUGCCUGUCCACCCACCCUGCGUGUCACUGUGGCGGCCUGGCUGUCGCUGCUUUUUGUCCUCUGCCGUGUUUGCGCGGCCUCAGUGCCCUCCCUGGUGCGUCUGCGCUGGGGCCCUCAGUGCUCGGGGCCUUGGGGUGCAUGGGUGCCGCCCUGGGCAGCUAGAGUGUCUCAGCCCGGUGCUGGGCCUGGCCGAGGGGCGGAGGCACAGCUGCUUCCAGCAGCCAGCAUUCAGUGGCCUUGUCACCAAGCUCCACACCUCCUCCUGGUGCUGGCUUUGGUGACAUCACAAGGCCCCUCCAGGUGCAGGGGCUUCUGUUUGGCAGGCCCCUGCCAGGGAGGACCUGGUGGCCUCCUCAUUCUCUUUUGCCAUUGGAAUGUCCCCUUGCAGUUCUCUUCUCUUUUUUUUUUUUUUUGAGAUGGAGUUUCACUCUUGCUGCCCAGGCUGGAGUGCAGUGGCUCAAUCUCGGGUCACUGCAACCUCCGCCUCCCGGGUUCAAGUGAUCGUCCUGCCUUAGGCUCCUGAGUAGCUGGGGAUUACAGGUGCCUACCAGCAUGCUCGGCUAAUUUUUUUGUAUUUUUAGUAGAGAAGGGAUUUCACCAUGUUGGCCGGGCUGGUCUCAAACUCCUAAGGUCAUCCACCUGCCUCGGCCUCCCAGAGUGCUGAGAUUACAGGCGUGAGCCUCCGCGCCCGGCCCCCUUGCAGUUCUCUCUGAUUUGGUUUGUUCUGUCUCAGGCUUCUGUGGCAGGACUGGCCCAGGGAGGAGGAAGCCAGCAGCACACCUGGGGAAUGGGGUCCCGGCCGGGAGGCUUGGCCUCUGGGCGACCUCGUCCUGUUUUUUUUGUUUGUUUGUUUGUUUUUUUAAAGGUAAACCUCCUGGGCCGCAGAUGGCAAAGGGAGUGCCUGGGCCUGGUGACCCAGGGCUGGAUCCACCCCUGCGGAGCCCUGGGCCAGGCAGGUGUCUGCUGCUCACCUGGCUCUGGAGGGCUGCCCUGCAGCUGGGCCUGGGGACAGGUCGGCUGUGGGGCAGCUCAGUACCCUCCCUGAGGCUCACGGUGGCUCCGAGCAUGAGGUCCGCCUCCUGGGCGAGACCCAGCAGUGGACAGCAUGGUCCUCACACCCAGCUCCCUGCACACCCAGGCCAGCCACCCCUCCCGCUCGUGCACAGGCACGCAGAUGCGCUCACACGUACACACACACAAAUGCACGCCCACUUGCACAUGCUCACGCACAUGUUCACACAUGCACACUCACGCUCACACAUGCUGUCACGCAUACACACACGCACAUACUCCUGCACAUGUUCCCAUGCAUGUGUGUGCACUCGGACCGAGCAUCUCCCACGCACCUCUACCCCACCCCAAGCACCUCUCUCCCCCCAUGCACCUCUCCCCAACAACACACACAGCCCCCUGCACCGCCCGCCCCCCGCCCCCACCAAGGCCCCAGCCUCUGGCCAUCAGUCCUGGUGCCAGAGCUUUGCGUGAAGUUCGGGCCGCAGAGUGGCCCGCUGGGACUCCCAUGUGCUGCCGUCUGAUGUGCUCAGAUGGGCUCAUCGUUGGUUCGUUUUUACUGUAUAUUUAUAGUAAUAAAAUCAUGCAGCAA